GUCAGAGCCUCGUGCCGGCUCGGCAGCGCCCGGACGCCGAGCCCAGCGCGUCGGCCCCCCGGCGUGCGGGCGUCUCAGAGCCGCGGAGGGGCCGCCGGGACCGUUUCAGCGUGGCGGCGCUGGUGCUGGCGUUGGCCCUGGAGGACGGCCCCGAGUGAUGGCUGGCGCCUGCCUCCCGGGUGUCUCCCGGGUACAGAUGGAGUCGUCCCGCGGCCGCCGGCGGCAAGGUCGGCAGCUGCGAGGCCAAGAGAGACCCCAGGACACACACAGCUGCCUCCCGGUGCGAGAAGAAGACCCCGGCUUGAGAGUGAGAUGGCGUUUAAUGAUUGCUUCAGUUUGAACUACCCUGGCAACCCCUGCCCAGGGGACUUGAUCGAAGUGUUCCGUCCUGGCUAUCAGCACUGGGCCCUGUACUUGGGUGAUGGUUACGUUAUCAACAUAGCACCUGUAGAUGGCAUUCCUGCGUCCUUUACAAGCGCCAAGUCUGUAUUCAGCAGUAAGGCCCUGGUGAAAAUGCAGCUCUUGAAGGAUGUUGUGGGAAAUGACACAUACAGAAUAAACAAUAAAUACGAUGAAACGUACCCCCCUCUCCCUGUGGAAGAAAUCAUAAAGCGGUCAGAGUUUGUAAUUGGACAGGAGGUGGCCUAUAACUUACUUGUCAACAACUGUGAACAUUUUGUGACAUUGCUUCGCUAUGGAGAAGGAGUUUCAGAGCAGAUAAUACAACUGAAGGACUCAAAGCCUAUAAAUAAAUGGCAGAACCAGAAUUCAAAGGAGAAUGGACUACCUCUUGGCCUGUGUACCUUUGACAGCCUCAUGGUGCCUACUGAGAAAUGUGCCCUGAAUCACAAAUACGAGACAGGACAUUUUGGAGGCUAUGUGUCUGUCUCCAUUUUUAUCUUUUCAAACAGAAGGCUAAGAUUAAAUCAUUCAUCAAAUAAUGUUAAUAUUUCCAAUUCUCCCAAAGCAAAUUCUACCUGGAAUUCAUUCUUUAAGGAGGACAGAGAAAUGUGGAGACAGUCUUAAUCAAGUUGUGAAAUACAGCAAAUUGUAAAGGGUUGUUUGGAUUAAAGGGUUGUUUGGAAAAGCUGGGUCAGAUUCUAGCAGAGAACCUGGCUCUUUUUCUCAUGGCUGCCACCACUCCAAUCCAGAACUAACUCUUCUCCAUCCCUUGACCUGGAAGUCACUUGAUUUUGAAUUAUUUGUUUGUUUGUUUAAUUUUGAGAUGGAGUCUCGCUCUCUCAGGCUGGAGUGCAGUGGCACAAUUUCAGCUCACUGCAACAUUCUCCUGCCUCAGCCUCCCAAGUAGCUGGGAAUACAGGCACCUGCCACGACACCCAGCUAAUUUUUAUAUUUUUAGUAGAGACGGGGUUUUACCAUGUUGGCCAGGCUGGUCUUGAACUCCUGACCUCAAGUGAUCCACCCGCCUUGGCCUCCUAGAGUGCAGGGAUUACAGGCAUGAGCCACCAUGCCUGACCCUGGAAUUAUUUAUUUAUGCAAUGGUCUUCUCCCCUAGCUUCUAAACUACUUGAGAGCAGUGACCACACCUUAUUCAUCUUUGUAACUCUAGUACCAAACUCACUCUGGAGCUUCGUGUUUGAUAAAUGAAUGACUUGGGUUUUCAUUUCCUAAUUGCUUGUCUCUCCUCUCACAUGUAGUCUUCCUGCCGUCAUCUAAUUAGUCUGUCUUCAGAGCCCUGCUGAGAAGCCUGCUCAGAUAGCUUCAUUCACUCCAUGUUGCCCUUGGCAUAAAGUCUAAACUUCUCUAGCUGCCUCCAUCCAUCCAUGCCUGCCUUUAUUAUUCAUUCUUGUUCAUACUCCACAGCACAUGGCCUCAGUUUUAGCCAGUCUUCUAGUGCUUGGGUAAGCCUUGCUUUUGAUUUCUGUCUCUGCCACCGUACAUUCAUUUGCAUUUCUAAAACAAAACCUCUUUCAGUCCUCUCUGCGUCUUAGGCUGUUCUUAUUGGGAAUAUCCCUACCUCCUACCUGGCAAAAUGUGGCCUAUUCUUUUGAACCCAGGUCAAGUUGCAUCUCAUCAAUGAAAUGCCUCCCAUGACAGCCACAGUCCACAGUGGGGCCUCCUUCUUCUAUGUUCUUCCCAGUUCUGUCUGUCUUCACACUCUUUUCAAGUAUGGAUAGCCUCAGGUAGCGUUCAAGUAUGUCUCAUCUUCACAACAAAUCUAUGACUCGGAGAUCAGGAGCCAACCCUUCUCUUUUAUUUCUCUCACAAUACGGGGUCCAAGAAUUAGUUCAAUAGCCUUGAUGAAUUAGAUUUUAACCCAGGGCAUCCUGGAUCAAAUUAUAUCCACUGAUAUAAAACUUCAUGUAGUCAAUAUCUGACAAAACAUGACUGUCUUAUAAGUCUAUGUUUUCUUUCCCUUUAUAACUACUUUAUAAAGGAUUUCUAUGAUAUGGUUUAUUUUUUUGAAAAUUGUACUUGGAAAAUUAUUGUAUUAUUGCAUUAAUUUUAUUGUAUUGGUAUAACAUAGCAUAAUAAAGUAUCCAAACAAUAUUUCAGGUAGGUACAGGAUAAAUGUACCCAAUAAUAUUAAUAAUAUGAAAACCAUUAGAGGCCAGUAUAGGUGAAAUCCAGAUAUCUUAUUUGCCCUUCUAGUAUAUAGAAAUAGCCUCACAGUAUUUGGUGGUCAAAGAGAAUACAGUAAUAAUUGACUUGUGAAUUACAAUGAAUACAUGGUCCAUGUACAUGAGUCAUGCCAGAUGUGCAAAUGAAUGCCACUUACCUCCAUUCCACGGUAUAUAACUUGAAAGUCAGAAAACAGAAUGAAAAUUGUGAGGCCCAAGGCAGCUAGCAGCAGAAAUGAAAAUAUAUCUGAGGAAAUACCAAACAUUAUUUUUAGAUGUUAAAAGAAUGUUUCAUAUAAUUUGGCACACAUUGCAGAAUCAAUUAUCUCUGUUGGGCAAAUACCAGAUAUAUCUUCAGAUGUUUUGAUAUAUCCUCAUAUGUUUUGAAAUAUGUUCUAAUGCUUAUAAGAUGAAGGUAAUAUCUUAGAAUCUUUCCUUGAAAGUCUGGAUGUAGAGACUGUUAAUCAAAUGUAUUAAAGUAACCUCCAUAAAGCAGCUGCCCUGGUGCACUAUCACUGCGUGUCCAGUGAGUUGUGCUUGCGUGGGAUAAACAGUCAGUGUUCUUGGCACCAUCUCAUUCUUCCCCGUUGCCUGGAGAAUAAAGUUCAGGGAUCCUCUAUUGACAUUCAAGGCCUUCCACAAUCUGGUCCCAAUCAGCCUUUCUAACCUGGUCUCUGACUGCUCUUCCUUAUGGGCAAUUGGAAAGGUAAACCAUAAAACCUCCAGCUUCCACGGAGGCCCAACACUCUCUAGCUUCUGUGUCUUUGUUAAAAAAAAAAAAAAAAAAAAA